AGGGCUCUGUUCAUAAUGCCUCCAUCCUCCAGCAAACACCAAGAGACCUUCUCCCUAUUUCUGCUCCUUCAUUCUUUGAUGGCUAACAUAGAAAAGGCUACCUCUCCUCUCCAGGACAAUCAGACAGUCUCAGAGAAACUUCAGGUUUGUGAUCCCCUUUUGUCCAUGAAAGGAGAUGAUGCAAUGGACAAAGUUUCCAGGAUUGGUAAAGCCUAGGUUGUAAUUCAAGUCCUAGGCUCCUUACUCAAAUCCACUGUUUUUCUACUAUGCCUGAGUUGCCUACCCCUUCUCAUAAAGGGAAAAGCUGUUCUUAUUUUCAAGGACUUUGCAGAAAGUAAAUAGGUGUAAUGAUAUGUAGUCAAAAUCAAGUGAAGCAGAUGGAUGUGUGCUGCUGAGAUCAGAACAAUAAUGCUUCCGAUCCACACUGCCUUUUUGAGCUAGCCUUGGGGAAAAAGUAAAACAUCAGAGAAAUGCUUUUGUCUCAUAUUAUGUAUUAUAGCACAGGAGCUGGCUAACUUAAUGUGGGUCUAAUCCAACAUUUCUGAGAUAUAAUGAGGGUGAAGCUGUUGUUUUCUUGUUUGGAAAGUUAAUUGACCCAAUCCAAGCAUCCUGUACAGCAUCCACAGCUUUAACACCACUGAACCUGUAUUCACACUUGCUUCUGUAACCAACUCGGGGGAAUCUGCCUGCCACUUUGGACAGCUCCAGUUUAGCCCUGUGCCAGGUAAACACUGCUGCUGCUCUCUGUACAGAGGAGCUAGGUAAUAAAAGGCACAUGAAAAUCUUCAACAGCCCCAGCAACUCCAGCACCUUCACUGGCUUCAUCCUCCUGGGCUUCCCUUGCCCCAGGGAGGGGCAGAUCCUCCUCUUUGUGCUCUUCACUGUUGUUUACCUCCUGACCCUCAUGGGCAAUGGUUCCAUCAUCUGUGCUGUGCACUGGGAUCAGAGACUCCACGCCCCCAUGUACAUCCUGCUCGCCAACUUCUCCUUCUUGGAGAUAUGUUAUGUCACCUCCACAGUCCCCAGCAUGCUGGCCAACUUCCUCUCUGACACCAAGAUCAUCUCGUUCUCUGGCUGCUUCCUCCAGUUCUACUUUUUCUUCUCCUUGGGCUCUACAGAAUGCUUUUUCCUGGCAGUUAUGGCAUUUGAUCGAUACCUUGCCAUCUGUCGGCCUCUACGCUAUCCAACCAUUAUGACCAGACGUCUCUGUACCAAUCUUGUGGUCAAUUGCUGGGUACUUGGUUUCAUCUGGUUCUUGAUUCCUAUCGUCAACAUCUCCCAAAUGUCCUUCUGUGGAUCUAGGAUUAUUGACCACUUCCUAUGUGACCCAGCUCCUCUUCUAACUCUCACUUGCAAAAAAGGCCCUGUGAUAGAGCUUGUCUUUUCUGUCUUAAGUCCUCUGCCUGUCUUUAUGCUCUUUCUCUUCAUUGUGGGGUCCUAUGCUCUGGUCGUGAGAGCUGUGUUGAGGGUCCCUUCAGCAGCUGGGAGAAGAAAGGCUUUCUCCACCUGUGGGUCUCACCUGGCUGUGGUUUCACUGUUCUACGGCUCAGUACUGGUCAUGUAUGGGAGCCCACCAUCUAAGAAUGAAGCUGGAAAGCAGAAGACUGUGACUCUGUUUUAUUCUGUUGUUACCCCACUGCUUAACCCUGUGAUAUAUAGUCUUAGGAACAAAGAUAUGAGAAAAGCUCUGAAGAAAUUUUGGGGAACAUAAAAUGUUAAUCAAAAAGGUCCUUGCGUAAUUAAUCUUGUCUUUAAUUUUGGGGUUUAAAAAAAAAACUGGUCUUGGCCAGGCGCGGUGGCUUACGCCUGUAAUCCCAGCACUUUGGGAGCCCGAGGCGGGUGGAUCACGAGGUCAGGAGAUCAAGACCACCCUGGCUAACACGGUGAAACCCUGUCUCUACUAAAAAAUACAAAAAAUUAGCCGGGCGUGGUGGCGGACGCCUGUAGUCCCAGCUACUCGGGAGGCUGAGGCAGGAGAAUGGCGUGAACCCGGGAGGCGGAGCUUGCAGUGAGCCGAGAUCGCGCCACUGCACUCAAGCCUGGGCGACAGAGCGAGACUCUGUCUCAGGAAAAAAAAAAAAAAAAAACUGGUCUUAUACAGUUAAUUGUUCAUCUUACUAUUGGCCAAAGCUAAAAUACCUGUGAGCAUGUUUCUGUUAUUUCUCCUUUCAGAUCUUGAUUAUUUGCCCAGUUGUGUAACAUGCCUCAAUGUUUUUUAAUUGACUGGUGGGCAUUGUAUUUUAAAAACUAUAAAGACAAUAUAUGCAGUAAUGAAGGUUUUGUUCUAGCAAGUAGAUGGAGUAGAGGCAGAUCACAUUGAUUCUAUUUAAGCACUACUUGUAUGUGUUUUUAAAAUGAUCUGUGCUCGUUUUAGUUUUACUCUUAGGGUGUGGCUCUUACUGCAGGAACAUAGCCUUUCUGAGACCUCAGGGACAAAUCUGGACUGUUUAGAAGGUCCCUCCGCUUCAGCUGAUCCUAGCCUCCUAUUUCAGUACUUCUUGAACCCCAUGACUCCUGAAACUUCCGCUUUGCUCUUUAGACUCUCAGCUUUUGUUUCUGCUAGCUAUUUUGGGGUCUCACCGUGUACACACAGCUUAGAAAUCCAAAAAUGCCUUGAAGGGGAAUUGCAUCAUAUUUUUAGCCUAGCUUCUGUGGUCCUUCCCUCUCCAGGAUUUCUCAAACGCCAGGUGCUUUGGCAACUUUCAAAUUCUCUACCUUCUCAGUUCAGUAAAACUACUGCUUUCUGCUCAGUCCUUAUUCCUCCUUUCCUCAUACUCUCCCAACCCAGUAAAUGGUCAAAUAUCCUCAGGGAAAUACACAUGGGGAAUGUGAAACUCACCUCCCUUUUCUUCCCUUCAUCUUGGACUGUAGCCCAUGAAGGCUUGCCUAUGUCAGUUGCUCUGAGUGCCUUCAAAUGGUUGUUUUAUGUAUUUUGUCCAGAUUUUACUGUUGAUAGAAAUUAUUUUGGGUUUAGUACAAGUUUUUCAGUCAUGACCAGAAAGUUUUUUCUAUUCUAUCUAGAUUCCAUACAUUCUCACUUCUUCCUUCACUUUCAGGAGAUUAUCAUGUAGCAUGUGUCUUCAAAAGCCCACAAAUCAGAGAGACAGGUGGAUAUAGAGGCUGGCAUAAACACAAAUCUGGGAUGCACACCUGCUUUUCUUUUCAUUGCAACCAGCAAAGAAUCCCUGAGGACUCUUCCCCUGCAGGAAGCAGGGGAAAGGUUACCUAUGGUAAAAUAAAUGAUAAAAUCAGGACCACAGAUUUUGGCCUUUUUUUAAUGGAAGGCACCCAGUAAUUGUAGAUCAGUAAAAAUAGUCACCCAGAAUUUGUAUUAGAAGCUUGGGCUAGUUCUCCUUGAACUUUCCCCUAGGCCUGGAGUGAAAGGUCAUGCUAUGAUUGAAGUGUCUUCACUAAUCCAAAUACCUGUUUUUCAGGUUAAAUAAAUAGGAAUUGGGAAUCAGGGAGCAAUUUGCUGAGGAUAAUGACUUAAUUCCAAAAAAAAAAAAAAAAAAAGUUCCUAUCCACCACCCUUUUAACUAGCCCAAGUUCCCUUUGCUUUGAAAAGUAACCCUGAAUUUCUCUUUAGGACUUCUCACUUAUUUGCCAGUCAUAUCACAAUAAGUUUGUUUCCUUAAUAUAAACGAAGCUCUGUAAAAUAGUAAGAGAACAGAACAGUAUCCCAGUAAGAAAAUGAGCAAAAGGAUAUAAACGAAUAACAUCCAGAAAAAGAUUCUUAAACAUGGAAAGGGCACUAACUAAUUCAUAAAAAGGUAAAAGUAGAAUAAGCCUAUAAAUAUAUCUCACUUUUUAUCUAUUAAAUUGACAAAGAUCAAGAAGUUUGAUUACACAUUGCGUGUCUGAGGAUUGUGAAAUGGGUUCUCUCACACUUAGCUGGUGGGCGUAUCAGCUUUACAAACUCUAUAUAGGGUGACAAGGCAACCUCUAUCAAAAUUUAGAAGACACAUAUCCUUUAAAACAGCACCUCAACUUUUAAGUUGUUUAACCUACAGAUAUUUUUACACAUGUGGGAAAUGUUUACUGCAGCAUUGUUGUAAUAGCAAAAUAUUGAGAAAAACAUCAGUUCCCAUUAAUAGAAGACUAGUAAAAUGAGCUAUGGUGAGUUAUACCAUGGAAUAUUAUGUCUUCAAUUUAUAAACUAUGAAGCAGUUCCAUAUGCAAUGAUAUAUAAUAUGUCCAAGACACACUGUUAAAUGAAAAAAGCAAAGUGAAUAGCAGAGUGUAUUGUAGCUGCCUUCCAUGGAAAUGUGUAUAUCUCCUGAAAGAGCUCCAAAAAACUGAUAACAAUGGUUGCUUCAGGCAAGAAGAAUUUUGUGUCUAAGGAACAAGAUAGUAAAGGAGACUUUUUUUUCAUAACUCCUUUUGUGCGUUCAAAUUCUUUAUCAUGUGCCUAUA